CCCACACGCCGAAGGGCUCCGAGGGGGUCAGGCCAAUCGGCAGCCGUCACCCCACACCCCAGCCCAUCACCACACUCAAGGGGCCGCUAAGACAGUGUCUCCUAAGUCUCGUCUCCUGUCCCCAGCGGCCUACAGCUCCCUGCAGGCUGGUGGCCGCUUACCUGGCCGCCGCUCCCGCUGCCGAUGUCAGGGUCAUGCAAGCGGCCUCUCGCGACCGUUACCCGAGGGAGCGCGCGCGCGCCCGGCGUCUCUCCAGUGAUUGGCUGCCCGGAAGGAGGCGGAGACAGCCUCGCAUGGCGCGCGCGUCCACCUCGCCGUUCCCCCUCGCGCAGCUCCAACCAAAGAGAGACAUCCAACCCCGGGGGAGUGACAAGGGGGCGGGAUUGCUGUGAAACUCUCUUCUCUGAUUGGCUCUCUGGGAGCCAGCCGCUGCCACGAGGGAAAGAAGCUUCAGUUUCUCGCAUGCGCAGUCCUCAGCCAGCAGAGCCACGUUCCUUAUGAGCACCGUGGGUUUAUUUCAUUUUCCUACACCACUGACCCGAAUAUGCCCGGCGCCAUGGGGACUCCGGCUUUGGGAGAAGCUGACGUUGUUAUCCCCAGGAAUAGCUGUCACUCCGGUCCAGAUGGCAGGCAAGAAGGACUACCCUGCACUGCUUUCCUUGGAUGAGAAUGAACUCGAAGAGCAGUUUGUGAAAGGACACGGUCCAGGGGGCCAGGCAACCAACAAAACCAGCAACUGCGUGGUGCUGAAGCACAUCCCCUCAGGCAUCGUUGUAAAGUGCCAUCAGACAAGAUCAGUUGAUCAGAACAGAAAGCUAGCUCGGAAAAUCCUACAAGAGAAAGUAGAUGUUUUCUACAAUGGUGAAAACAGUCCUGUUCACAAAGAAAAACGAGAAGCGGCGAAGAAAAAACAAGAAAGGAAAAAAAGAGCAAAGGAAACCCUGGAAAAAAAGAAGCUACUUAAAGAACUGUGGGAGUCAAGUAAAAAGGUCCACUGAGAAAAGAAUUAGAGAUUCCAACUGACAGAAUCUGCCAGAAGCUCCCAGGGAAUAAUGGUGGCGAGUUCCAUCACCAGCAUUAUUAUAGUGCUUCAAAAGAAAUAUUUUUGAUGAACUUAAAAGACAACAAAUUUAUUUAAAUGGUGCACUAAACUGUAGUGAACAGAGACAUGCACGAUUCAAGAAUAAAACUCGGCUGGGCACGGUGGACGGUGCCUCACAUCUGUAAUCCCAGCACUUUGGGAGGCCGAGGCGGGCGGAUCACUUGAGGUCAGGAGUUUGAGACCAGCCUGGCCAACAUGGUGAAACCCCGUCUCUACUAAAAAUACAAAAAAUUAGCCAGGCAUGGUGGCGGGCACCUGUAAUCCCAGCUACUCGGGAGGCCGAGGCAGGAGAAUUGCGUGAACCUGGGAGGCGGAGGUUGCAGUGAGCUGAGAUCGCGCCACUGCACUCAAGCCUGGGCAACACCUGGGUGACAGAGCGAGACCCCAUCUCAAAAAAAAAAUAAAACUAGUUCAAGUGCAAUGACACACGCCUAUAAUCCCAGCACCUUGGGAGGCUAAGACAGGAAGAUCACCUGAGCCCAGGAGCUCAAGAUUGCAGUGAGCUAUGAACACCACUGCACUCCACCUGUCCACUUGUUCUUGUGUGACAGAACAAGACCCUGUCUCUAAAAAAUAAGAUAAAACCAUAAAGAAACACAGUCAGUACUAUACAAGAAUAAUGGCUACUUCUAGAGGGAAGGAGUUGUCAUUGUGAUGAGGCACUUGGAGGGGUUCUGGGGUGCCUGACAAAGUUCUGUUUCUUCACCUGGGUGGUAGUUAGAAGGGUGUCCCCGUAUUUCAAAUUGUACCUUUGUGAGAUUGUAUGUUUUGUAAUAAUAAAAUUUUUUUUGUAAUUAGUAAAGUCAAUUUUUAUGGAGAACUGGA